CUCUCCGCUGGCCACCUGCUGCCGCCCGCGCCAUGGCUGGCAAAGCACACAGGCUGAGCGCUGAGGAGAGGGACCAGCUGCUGCCAAACCUGAGGGCUGUGGGGUGGAAUGAGCUGGAAGGCCGUGAUGCCAUCUUCAAGCAGUUUCAUUUCAAAGACUUCAACAGGGCCUUUGGGUUCAUGACAAGAGUGGCCCUGCAGGCUGAGAAACUGGACCACCAUCCUGAAUGGUUUAACGUGUACAACAAGGUCCACAUCACGCUGAGCACCCAUGAGUGUGCCGGCCUUUCAGAACGGGACAUAAACCUGGCCAGCUUCAUCGAACAAGUAGCAGUGUCCAUGACAUAGACCCUGCCCUUCCUCUUUGAAUUCUUCCGGGGGAAGGGGUGACUGAACUGGGAGUCCAGGGAGGGAGCUGAGGAGCCCUUACCCUCCCACCACUCCCCUCCCAAGACCCAGCCGCCGCCGUUGAGGGCUGAGUCCUUGCUGUGGGAUGUGCCAGUGUCCCCACCAACACCAGGAAUUUAGACCUUUUCCCUGCACCACUCUCUUCAUCCUGGGGGCUCUGUUACACUAAUUUGAAUAAACUCUCCCCUUUCUUUGCAACUUCCCAGCAACAAUAAUGAUUUUCUUGCCAGGCCGUCUCUUGCUCCCUAAUUCAUUUCCCAGGAAGCUGUGAUACAGGGUGAAAUAAAGUCUUGUCUUAGAAACCAGGACCCUAAACCCCACACUAUGUAAUAGAAACACAUGUGUUUUUAUGUCUCAAAUAAAACUAUUAUAUCACUUGG